GUCUCACUCCUGUCAUUCAGGCUGGAGUGCAAUGGCGAGAUCUCAGCUGACUGCAACCUCCAUCUCCUGGGUUCAAGCGAUUCUCCUGUCUCAGCCUCCUGAGUAGCUGGCGCUAUAGGUGCCUGCCACCACACCUGGGUUAUAAACAACUUGUGAAAUGAGUGAUUUGGAAGAUGAUGAGACACCCCAGCUUUCUGCCCAUGCCUUAGCAGCUCUCCAGGAAUUUUAUGCUGAGCAAAAGCAACAAAUUGAGCCAGGCGAGGAUGAUAAAUAUAACAUUGGAAUAAUAGAAGAGAAUUGGCAACUGAGCCAGUUUUGGUAUAGUCAGGAAACUGCUCUGCAGCUGGCACAGGAGGCAAUUGCAGCUGUAGGAGAAGGUGGCAGAAUCGCAUGUGUGAGUGCCCCUAGUGUUUACCAGAAACUCAGAGAGCUGUGCAGAGAAAACUUUUCGAUAUACAUCUUUGAAUAUGACAAAAGAUUUGCCAUGUAUGGAGAGGAGUUUAUUUUCUAUGAUUACAAUAAUCCAUUGGACUUACCCGAAAGAAUUGCUGCACAUAGUUUUGACAUCGUAAUAGCAGAUCCUCCCUAUCUUUCGGAGGAAUGUCUCAGAAAAACAUCGGAAACCGUCAAGUACCUGACGCGGGGCAAGAUUCUGCUGUGCACAGGUGCCAUCAUGGAAGAACAGGCAGCAGAACUCCUUGGAGUGAAGAUGUGCACGUUUGUUCCAAGACACACCCGGAACUUGGCAAAUGAGUUUCGCUGUUAUGUGAAUUAUGAUUCUGGGCUGGACUGUGGGAUCUGAUUACAGACGGUGACAUAACACAGGAAGGAACCCUGUCACAUUCCUCUUUUUGUAUUUUCGUAGUAGAUUUAAAAGUUAUAAUCUCUUCCCCUCCCCCCAAACUGGAGCUGUCCCUGGCCUGGUUUUCAAAAUAAAGUGUGCGAUCUUCAUUAUUGUUUCCUUAGGGAGGGCGUCCCUAGAGCUCAGUCUUCUGCCAACCUGAAUCCAUGGAAUUCGAGUUGGAAGAAACCUUAGAAUCUGCCUGAUCUUCUCUCCUCAUUUAACAUGUGUAAAAACAGAAGAACAGUUGUGUGGCUUGCCCAAGGGCUCCUGAAUGAGACAGGACCUUGGCCUCUGCCUCGGGCCAGAG